CUUUUUCGUCCUUUUCCCCGGUUGCUGCUUGCUGUGAGUGUCUCUAGGGUGAUACGUGGGUGAGAAAGGUCCUGGUCCGCGCCAGAGCCCAGCGCGCCUCGUCGCCAUGCCUCGGAAAAUUGAGGAAAUCAAGGACUUCCUGCUCACAGCCCGACGAAAGGAUGCCAAAUCUGUCAAGAUCAAGAAAAAUAAGGACAACGUGAAGUUUAAAGUUCGAUGCAGCAGAUACCUUUACACCCUGGUCAUCACUGACAAAGAGAAGGCAGAGAAACUGAAGCAGUCCCUGCCCCCCGGUUUGGCAGUGAAGGAACUGAAAUGAACCAGACACACUGAUUGGAACUGUAUUAUAUUAAAAUACUAAAAAUCCUAAGUGUCUUUCGUCUUUGCGGAUGGGAAAGGGAAAAAUGCUACCUCGUAGUGGCUUCUGAUGGGAACAGGACGCGGGUUCUGUUGCUGCCUUCCUGUGUCUUUUUUUUUUUUUUUUUUUCUUUCUUUGAGACGGAGUCUUGCUCUGUGGCUCAUCCUGGAGCACAGUGGUGCGAUAUCAGCUCACUACCACCUCCGCCUCCUGGGUUCAAGCGACUGUCCUGCCUCAGCCUCCCGAGUGGCUGGGAUUACAGGCACACAUCACCACGCCUGGCCAAUUUUUGUAUUUGUAGUAGAGACAGGGUUUCACUGCCUGCCUCAGCCUCCCAUAGUGCUGGGAUUACAGGCAUGAGCCUCCGUGCCCGGUGCAUCCCUAAUCUUGAGCAUGAUCUCAGUCGGCAAAUGAGGCCAUCUGUUUUCAGCCUGUUUGAAAAUAAGAUGUGGGGAGGCCAUGAUGGAAAUAGCACGUGGGGUUAAACAUAACUGGCAGAUGUGGGAGCGAUGGUGGGGCAUGCCAUUCAAACAGGUCCCAAAAUGGGUGCAACAAGGUAUAGCACAUCUACCACUCGCUAACUUGACUGACUUGGAGAAAUGACUACACUUUUGCCUGUUUCCUCAGUUGGAAAAUAGCCAUAUUAACACCUCUUUCAUUGGCUUGCUGUCAGGGUACUGGGAUGGGGGGAGGUGCAUGGGUUGGGGUGGCCACCAGGUGGUGCUGUGCCACAGCGGGCAGCCCCUCUGGAAAUGACUGGCAUCAUAAAAUCUGUCUUCAUACCCGA